AGAAUCUGGGUGUUUGAGCCCUAAAGUCAUACAGCAAGUAGUCCACCUGGAAUCAUGAACCAGGUCUUCAGGACUUCCAGAUAUUUGUGCUGUAUACUAUGCUGCAUUUUCAACAAUAAUUCAUUUAUCUGUGGGUUUGAUUUAAUGAGACUCAUUUAUUCAACAAAUAUUUAUUAAAUGCUAUUCUUGCCAGUCAUUGUGUUAAAUGAUAGUGUAACACAGUAAACAAGACAGAUAUCUUUCCAUGUCCUCACGAAACCAGCAGCUUUGGAACUAAACAAAUAAUUAUAACUAAGAUGAGCAUUAAGGGAGAAAUUGUAAGAUGAUAGGAAAGAAUAUAACAGGCGGACUUAACCUGCUCUGGGAUGGUGGGGGAGUGUUGAAUGUGAACUGAGGGUAGGACAUGAGAAAUAACUUUUGGGCUGAGAUUGGAAGAAUCAGCAUGAGUUAGCUUAAGCCUAGGAAUUAGGAGAAGGGUUAGGAUGGAACAUUGCAGGCAACAGAAAUAGCAUCUACAAAAGUAAAAGGAAGAACUGAAAAGAUUCCAGUGUGAGCGUUGAAAAGAAGGAUAAGUAAAUGUAGAGAAGAAUGUAGGAAAGAGAUUAUGCAUUCUUCAGGAUUUUUUGACCUAUAUCCUAAGGGAUAUUGGGAAACCAUGGAAAGGUUUUAAGCAUCGGGGUAUGCCAUGAUUAAAUUUUUCAUUUGAAAAUCAUGAGUCUGACUAUAGUAUAUAUAGAAGCAUUGUUGUUAGAUGCUAUUUCGGUAGGCCAGGUUGGAGAUGAUGGUUACAGCAGUGGAGCUGGAGAGAAGGGAAUAGAUUUGAAAUUUGGGAUGUGAACAAAGCCUUGUAUUUGACAGAAAUGUAAAACUAUUAAUAGUAUUGUUAUUGUUCCACCUAUAGAAUCUGAUUAUAAGAUUAUCUCUAAAAUACUUUCAGGUAACUUGUACUUAAUGUUAGGAGGAAGUGACUAUAUUAUAAAUAUAAUUUAGAAAACAUCGUUCCUUAAAAAAUAAUUUUUGAAUUGUGCUAAUUCUUGUUAUUGUUUGACUUCAUUAACUAAUAUAGGGAGUAUAGGGAGAACUUAGUUUUAAAAGAUAAUUUGACUUCCUGAUUUAUACAUAAAACACAUAAGUAAUUUUGGACAUAUAUGAUGUGUAUAUAUAUAUAUAUAUAGUGCAGGUCAUCUUGUUUACACCACUUAUUAAUGAAUAUCAGAUUUGGAAGGUGACUCUUUAGGAUUUUCCUAUUGGUUGAUUGAUUGAAACUUACAUGAAGAAUUUAACCCUUUUGUUUCAAAUAGCUUUCUAUUAAGAAACACUUUUUUCAUGAUUAUUCAGAGAAUUUAUUGCUGGAUCAUUGGCUCUAGAGAUAGACUGCUGGUUAAAUUAAAAGAUGCCGGAGGAAACAUUUUGGAAACAGACUUCACAGAAUUCCUUAUGAACUUCUGUACUUUCUUAACCAAUCUUAUUUCUUUCAUGUACCUAUGGCUGUUACUAGCCUGUUGUAUCAGGGAUACCAUAGUCAACUACCUAUACGGGCCUUAACUAUAAAGAAUUAGGCCAUUUAGGGAAAUAAUAAUGAGACUGGGGCUUUAGAGAAUUUGUGCUCAUCUAACUGAGUAGAGGGACAGCUAAUAUUCUGCUCCAUCUGAUGGUGAUCAUGGGAGUAUUCAGGCUGAUUGUUACCCAAUAUUUCAGUUUUUCCAAAGGAUCCUAAAAUACAGAUUUUUAUGUAAAUUAGUUGGUAAUUAAUUUAGGUGUUUUUAAGAUACUCUGUGACAAUAACUCUACAGGGCAAAAUCGACCUGUUAAAUAUAUUUGGCCCAUAGGCUGUUGUUUUAUAGCCUUGACCAUAUAGAAAUCUUCAAUAUCUAUUUAAAAGUAAGAGGUCAAAAGUAUUUCUAGGAAAAGUGAAUGCCAAAAGAAGGGAGGAAGGGAAGGCAUAAAUGAGAUACUUUUUAAAAGAAGUACAAAACUAGUUAUCUAGGUUAUAUUUUUAAACUAAGUUCAAAAAGAAAUUCACUGUCCUGAGAAUAAUUUUCAUAUGCUUCAGAACAUACUUCUAGCAACUUCAGCCAUCUGCGUGUGUAUAACUGGGAACUCAGAGUAGGAUGAGAAUGCACAGGGCGUAGAGAACCAAUGAACUGUAGAUGAGAGUGUAGUGGUUCUCUGAAACUGUUGUGAGCAGAGUACAGCAGGAACAAGAGACAGUUGAUAUUGGAGCAAAAUCAGGCUAUAAGAACAUAGCGAUCUGAGUACAUCAUGGGCCCCUGAAAGCAUUACUAGACUAAAAGCAUAAUUUUUUAUACUGAUGAUCAAGAAGAGGUCAUAUUGGUACACUAAGAUUGAAUAACUCUGCUCCCAAUAGCACAUGUAAUACACAAUCACUGUAGGAAAUCAGGAAAAUAUACAAAAAGUAGCAUAUGGUUUUUUUUUAAAGCUAGGAAUGGGUAAAAUUCUAAAGUUUUCUAAAAGUAAUGAAAAUAGAACUUGGCAAUUGUUAGUUUCCUAAUAGCUAAUUAGUUUCCAAAUUAGUCUAAUUUGGCUUAAAUAAAAAGAAUAUUGGUUAGCUCACAUAAGAAAAUACAUAUAUUAGGAUUAGUUACGCCAGUGGCUCAGUGAUUUUUUUCAAGGACUCAGUUUGUCGUCUACUCUACUCUUUAUCCAUAAUAUUUCCUUUAUCCCAACACUGUAGUUGCCAAAUGGCUGCUGGCUGCAAUCAGGAUUGUGUGUUUCCUCCUUCAGAUCCAAAGAGAGAAAUAAACUUCUCUUGGCGUUCUCAUGGGCAAUAUAGGUUCUUUUCUCUGAGAAGUCCUUAUGCACUCCUGCCCCCAACUUGCUCCUUAUUGUCCUAAAUUAGCUUAAUUCUAAAUAUGCCUUAACUAAUCGUUGGCAAAAGGGAUGAGCUUACCAUAAUGGAUUAGAUUAAUUGUGGUCUACCCUUGCAGCUCAGGACAGUCAGCUUACCCUGAGGCGCAUUGACCACUGGGAGAGAUGUGGAUAUAGAAAUCCAAUCAUGGAUCAUUAGGAAGAAGGAAGCGUUGGAUAGGCUCUCAGCAUGGUCCACCACAGUUGCAUUAAGGAUUGUGUAUUACGUUUUUUACUUAUGUGAAACACCACCUUCCCCCAUCAAGCCUUUUUCAGUUUAAAUUCUCAACUGGCAAUUGGCCGAAAACUCCCAUCUGAAGACAUGAUCAUCCAAAUGUCAUUUUGUGAUUUGGCUACUGUCUGCUUGACAUAGGAAAGCACUAUCAAGAAAGACUAAUGGAGUGACUAUCAAAAGGAAGUCAAUGAUUUCUUAAGAAUUUACAACAAAACCCUGUCAAAGCAGCAUUCUUACGUGAGAAUUUCACUUACGGGAGAGUUCUUACAGGAUUUCAAGAAGGAAAGCCCUGAAGAGGGACACUGAUUUCCUCAACUGAAUUUAAAAUUGUUACAUGCAGACAUUUUUAAAGGACAACCUUAAACUUCCACCACAAGAGGAAUAUAAAGAGGUCCCUCCUGCACCAAGAAAGAUCUGCAGAUCUUUUUCAGUGUUCUUGGAGGUGUGGGGUGUGAGAACUUGAUCAGUUUGUGUCAGCCACCUUGUUCUCUAAAGGGAAAGCCCCUCAAACCAUUUUGUAUUCUGUAUUACACUUCAGAAAGUGUGGAAGCAAAGGUCAUCUAAUCUUUAAAAGUUACAAAUUAUAAUACUGUGGUAGAAACAAAUUCAGAUUCAGAUGAUGAAGACAAACUGCAUAUUGUGGAAGAAGAAAGUGUUACAGAUGCAGCUGACUGUGAAGGUGUACCAGAGGAUGACCUGCCAACAGACCAGACAGUGUUACCAGGGAGGAGCAGUGAAAGAGAAGGGAAUGCUAAGAACUGCUGGGAGGAUGACACAGGAAAGGAAGGGCAAGAAAUCCUGGGGCCUGAAGCUCAGGCAGAUGAAGCAGGAUGUACAGUAAAAGAUGAUGAAUGCGAGUCAGAUGCAGAAAAUGAGCAAAACCAUGAUCCUAAUGUUGAAGAGUUUCUACAACAACAAGACACUGCUGUCAUUUUUCCUGAGGCACCUGAAGAGGACCAGAGGCAGGGCACACCAGAAGCCAGUGGUCAUGAUGAAAAUGGAACACCAGAUGCAUUUUCACAAUUACUCACCUGUCCAUAUUGUGAUAGAGGCUAUAAACGCUUUACCUCUCUGAAAGAACACAUUAAAUAUCGUCAUGAAAAGAAUGAAGAUAACUUUAGUUGCUCCCUGUGCAGUUACACCUUUGCAUACAGAACCCAACUUGAACGUCACAUGACAUCACAUAAAUCAGGAAGAGAUCAAAGACAUGUGACGCAGUCUGGGUGUAAUCGUAAAUUCAAAUGCACUGAGUGUGGAAAAGCUUUCAAAUACAAACAUCACCUAAAAGAGCACUUAAGAAUUCACAGUGGAGAGAAGCCAUAUGAAUGCCCAAACUGCAAGAAACGCUUUUCCCAUUCUGGCUCCUAUAGCUCACACAUAAGCAGUAAGAAAUGUAUCAGCUUGAUACCUGUGAAUGGGCGACCAAGAACAGGACUCAAGACAUCUCAGUGUUCUUCACCGUCUCUUUCAGCAUCACCAGGCAGUCCCACACGACCACAGAUACGGCAAAAGAUAGAGAAUAAACCCCUUCAAGAACAACUUUCUGUUAACCAAAUUAAAACUGAACCUGUGGAUUAUGAAUUCAAACCCAUAGUGGUUGCUUCAGGAAUCAACUGUUCAACCCCUUUACAAAAUGGGGUUUUCACUGGUGGUGGCCCAUUACAGGCAACCAGUUCUCCUCAGGGCAUGGUGCAAGCUGUUGUUCUGCCAACAGUUGGUUUGGUGUCUCCCAUAAGUAUCAAUUUAAGUGAUAUUCAGAAUGUACUUAAAGUGGCGGUAGAUGGUAAUGUAAUAAGGCAAGUGUUGGAGAAUAAUCAAGCCAAUCUUGCAUCCAAAGAACAAGAAACAAUCAAUGCUUCACCCAUACAACAAGGUGGCCAUUCUGUUAUUUCAGCCAUCAGUCUUCCUUUGGUUGAUCAAGAUGGAACAACCAAAAUUAUCAUCAACUACAGUCUUGAGCAGCCUAGCCAACUUCAAGUUGUUCCUCAAAAUUUAAAAAAAGAAAAUCCAGUCGCUACAAACAGUUGUAAAAGUGAAAAGUUACCAGAAGAUCUUACUGUUAAGUCUGAGAAGGACAAAAGCUUUGAAGGGGGGGUGAAUGAUAGCACUUGUCUUCUGUGUGAUGAUUGUCCAGGAGAUAUUAAUGCACUUCCAGAAUUAAAGCACUAUGACCUAAAGCAGCCUACUCAGCCUCCUCCACUCCCUGCAGCAGAAGCUGAGAAGCCUGAGUCCUCUGUUUCAUCAGCUACUGGAGAUGGCAAUUUGUCUCCUAGUCAGCCACCUUUAAAGAACCUCUUGUCUCUCCUAAAAGCAUAUUAUGCUUUGAAUGCACAACCAAGUGCAGAAGAGCUCUCAAAAAUUGCUGAUUCAGUAAACCUACCACUGGAUGUAGUAAAAAAGUGGUUUGAAAAGAUGCAAGCUGGACAGAUUUCAGUGCAGUCUUCUGAACCAUCUUCUCCUGAACCAGGCAAAGUAAAUAUCCCUGCCAAGAACAAUGAUCAGCCUCAAUCUGCAAAUGCAAAUGAACCCCAGGACAGCACAGUAAAUCUACAAAGUCCUUUGAAGAUGACUAACUCCCCAGUUUUACCAGUGGGAUCAACCACCAAUGGUUCCAGAAGUAGUACACCAUCCCCAUCACCUCUAAACCUUUCCUCAUCCAGAAAUACACAGGGUUACUUGUACACAGCUGAGGGUGCACAAGAAGAGCCACAAGUAGAACCUCUUGAUCUUUCACUACCAAAGCAACAGGGAGAAUUAUUAGAAAGGUCAACUAUCACUAGUGUUUACCAGAACAGUGUUUAUUCUGUCCAGGAAGAACCCUUGAACUUGUCUUGCGCAAAAAAGGAGCCACAAAAGGACAGUUGUGUUACAGACUCAGAACCAGUUGUAAAUGUAAUCCCACCAAGUGCCAACCCCAUAAAUAUCGCUAUACCUACAGUCACUGCCCAGUUACCCACAAUCGUGGCCAUUGCUGACCAGAACAGUGUUCCAUGCUUAAGAGCGCUAGCUGCCAAUAAGCAAACGAUUCUGAUUCCCCAGGUGGCAUACACCUACUCAACUACGGUCAGCCCUGCAGUCCAAGAACCACCCUUGAAAGUGAUCCAGCCAAAUGGAAAUCAGGAUGAAAGACAAGAUACUAGCUCAGAAGGAGUAUCAAAUGUAGAGGAUCAGAAUGACUCUGAUUCUACACCGCCCAAAAAGAAAAUGCGGAAGACAGAAAAUGGAAUGUAUGCUUGUGAUUUGUGUGACAAGAUAUUCCAAAAGAGUAGUUCAUUAUUGAGACAUAAAUAUGAACACACAGGUAAAAGACCUCAUGAGUGUGGAAUCUGUAAAAAGGCAUUUAAACACAAACAUCAUUUGAUUGAACACAUGCGAUUACAUUCUGGAGAAAAGCCCUAUCAAUGUGACAAAUGUGGAAAGCGCUUCUCACACUCUGGGUCUUAUUCUCAACACAUGAAUCAUCGCUACUCCUACUGUAAGAGAGAAGCGGAAGAACGUGACAGCACAGAGCAGGAAGAGGCAGGGCCUGAAAUCCUCUCGAAUGAGCACGUGGGUGCCAGGGCGUCUCCCUCACAGGGCGACUCGGACGAGAGAGAGAGUUUGACAAGGGAAGAGGAUGAAGACAGUGAAAAAGAGGAAGAGGAGGAGGAUAAAGAGAUGGAAGAAUUGCAGGAAGAAAAAGAAUGUGAAAAACCACAAGGGGAUGAGGAAGAGGAGGAGGAGGAGGAAGAAGUGGAAGAAGAAGAGGUAGAAGAGGCAGAGAAUGAGGGAGAAGAAGCAAAAACUGAAGGUCUGAUGAAGGAUGACAGGGCUGAAAGUCAAGCAAGCAGCUUAGGACAAAAAGUAGGCGAGAGUAGUGAGCAAGUGUCUGAAGAAAAGACAAAUGAAGCCUAAUCGUUUUUCUAGAAGGAAAAUAAAUUCUAAUUGAUAAUGAAUUUCGUUCAAUAUUAUCCUUGCUUUUCAUGGAAACACAGUAACCUGUAUGCUGUGAUUCCUGUUCACUACUGUGUAAAGUAAAAACUAAAAAAAUACAAAAUACAAAACACACACACACACACACACACACACACACACACACACACAAAAUAAAUCCGGGUGUGCCUGAACCUCAGACCUAGUAAUUUUUCAUGCAGUUUUCAAAGUUAGGAACAAGUUUGUAACAUGCAGCAGAUUAGAAAACCUUAAUGACUCAGAGAGCAACAAUACAAGAGGUUAAAGGAAGCUGAUUAAUUAGAUAUGCAUCUGGCAUUGUUUUAUCUUAUCAGUAUUAUCACUCUUAUGUUGGUUUAUUCUUAAGCUGUACAAUUGGGAGAAAUUUUAUAAUUUUUUAUUGGUAAACAUAUGCUAAAUCCGCUUCAGUAUUUUAUUAUGUUUUUUAAAAUGUGAGAACUUCUGCACUACAAAAUUCCCUUCACAGAGAAGUAUAAUGUAGUUCCAACCCGUGCUAACUACCUUUUAUAAAUUCAGUCUAGAAGGUAGUAAUUUCUAAUAUUUAGAUGUCUUAGUAGAGCGUAUUAUCAUUUAAAGUGUAUUGUUAGCCUUAAGAAAGCAGCUGAUAGAAGAACUGAAGUUUCUUACUCACGUGGUUUAAAAUGGAGUUCAAAAGAUUGCCAUUGAGUUCUGAUUGCAGGGACUAACAAUGUUAAUCUGAUAAGGACAGCAAAAUCAUCAGAAUCAGUGUUUGUGAUUGUGUUUGAAUAUGUGGUAACAUAUGAAGGAUAUGACAUGAAGCUUUGUAUCUCCUUUGGCCUUAAGCAAGACCUGUGUGCUGUAAGUGCCAUUUCUCAGUAUUUUCAAGGCUCUAACCCGCCUUCAUCCAAUGUGUGGCCUACAAUAACUAGCAUUUGUUGAUUUGUCUCUUGUAUCAAAAUUCCCAAAUAAAACUUAAAACCACUGACUCUGUCAGAGAAACUGAAACACUGGGACAUUUCAUCCUUCAAUUCCUCGGUAUUGAUUUUAUGUUGAUUGAUUUUCAGAAUUUCUCUACAGAAACGAAAGGGAAAUUUUCUAAUCUGCUUUAUCCAUGUACUUGCAUUUCAGACAUGGACAUGCUAUUGUUAUUUGGCUCAUAACUGUUUCCAAAUGUUAGUUAUUAUGGACCCAAUUUAUUAACAACAUUAGCUGAUUUUUACCUAUCAGUAUUAUUUUAUUUCUUUUAGUUUAUAGAUCUGUGCAACAUUUUUGUACUGUAUGUCUUCAAACCUGGCAGUAUUAAUACCCUUCUUACUGACAUAUGUACUUUUAGUUUUAGAAAACUUUUAUAUUUAUGUGUCUUAUUUUUAUAUUUCUUUAUUUAUUACACAGUGUAGUGUAUAAUACUGUAGUUUGUAUUAAUACAAUAAUAUAUUUUAGUAUGAAAAUUUGGAAAGUUGAUAAGAUUUAAAGUAGAGAUGCAAUUGGUUCUCCUGCAUUGAGAUUUGAUUUAACAGUGUUAUGUUAACAUUUAUACUUGCCUUGGACUGUAGAACAGAACUUAAAUGGGAAUGUAUUAGUUUUACAACUACAAUCAAGUCAUUUUACCUUUACCCAGUUUUUAAUAUAAAACUUAAAUUUUGAAAUUCACUGUGUGACUAAUAGCAUGAUGCUCUGCAGUUUUAUUAAGAAAUCAGCCUAACCAUACAACUCUCAUUUCCUUAGUAAGCCAAAUUAGGAUUAACUUCUAUAAACAGUGUUGGGAACAAUGUUUAACAUUUUGUGCCAAUUUGUUCCUGUAUUCAUGUAUGUAAGUUACAGAUCUGACUCUUCAUUUUUAAGUUCCUUGUUACAUCAUGGUCAUUUUCUAGUUUUUUACCAGACUCCCAUCUCACAAUAAAAUGCAUCAACAAGCCUGAACUGCUGUCAUUCUUUUCAUCAUUAUCAGUAUUUUCUUUGGAAAACUGUGAAAUGGGGUACAUUGUCAUCCUGCAUUUGAUUCAUCUUGAGCUGAAUUUGGGUAACACUAAAUGUUUUAGACAUUCUCCACUAAAUUAUGGAUUUUCUUGUGGCUAAAUGUUUCUGGAGAGGUCAGAGUUGACAAAACCUCUUCACAGGUUGCUCCUUCUUCCUGAAAUCCUUAAUCCUCCGCAUUUCAUGCUUCAGGUCAUUUCAGGGAAGCCUGGGUUUAGAUGCCUUUCUGACUCUCAGCUCCUGCACUUCUGUCAUCAUACCUCUGAUACUAUUAUUUAUAUUCCUUCCCCACUAGGAACAGGAACCACAUUUGUCAUAGUCACUCUCACAUUCCUCACUGCCUAACAGGGUGCCUGGCAUAAGUUGGGACAACAGAUAUUUGUUGAAUAAAAAUAUAAUUUGCAUGUUUAUGGAGCUCAGCUAUGUUCUCACUUUUUUUGCUUCUAAUUCCAGAAUAUAUGUUAAAUGAUCUAAUAAUUUGAUUAUUUUCUUAUAAGUCUUAUUAAACACUAGUCAUAAUAGACACAAUAAAUUAUGCCUUCUUUUUC